GCUACGGGUAGCUGGGUGCUGUCCAAAGGCGACAGGGCGUCGUUAGGGGAGCGAGUCGUGACCGGUUGGGCCACACUCAACGUGGGACGAAGCUUCGCCUACUGUUUGACUACGUGCGUGCAGCCUCCCCUCGAUGUCGGCCCUCGAAAAGAGCAUGCACCUCGGCCGCCUUCCCUCUCGCCCACCUCUACCCGGCAGCGGGGGCAGUCAGAGCGGAGCCAAGAUGCGAAUGGGCCCUGGAAGAAAGCGGGACUUUUCCCCUGUUCCUUGGAGUCAGUAUUUUGAGUCCAUGGAAGAUGUAGAAGUAGAGAAUGAAACUGGCAAGGAUACUUUUCGAGUCUACAAGAGUGGUUCAGAGGGUCCAGUCCUGCUCCUUCUGCAUGGAGGAGGUCAUUCUGCCCUUUCUUGGGCUGUGUUCACGGCAGCGAUUAUUAGUAGAGUUCAGUGUAGGAUUGUAGCUUUGGAUCUGCGAAGUCAUGGUGAAACAAAGGUCAAGAAUCCUGAAGAUCUGUCUGCAGAAACAAUGGCAAAAGACGUUGGCAAUGUGGUUGAAGCCAUGUAUGGGGACCUUCCUCCUCCAAUUAUGCUGAUUGGACAUAGCAUGGGUGGUGCUAUUGCAGUCCACACAGCAUCAUCCAACCUGGUACCAAGCCUCUUGGGUCUGUGCAUGAUUGAUGUUGUAGAAGGUACAGCUAUGGAUGCACUUAAUAGCAUGCAGAAUUUCUUACGGGGUCGUCCUAAAACCUUCAAGUCUCUGGAGAAUGCUAUUGAAUGGAGUGUGAAGAGUGGCCAGAUUCGAAAUCUGGAGUCUGCCCGUGUCUCAAUGGUUGGCCAAGUCAAACAGUGUGAAGGAAUUACAAGUCCAGAAGGCUCAAAAUCUAUAGUGGAAGGAAUCAUAGAGGAAGAAGAAGAAGAUGAGGAAGGAAGUGAGUCUAUAAGCAAGAGGAAAAAGGAAGAUGACAUGGAGUGAAACAAUGGGAGAUAAUGCAAGGCCUGUGGUGGAUGCCCUUGUGUGGAGAACUGCAUCUCGCCCAGGUAAACAUCCCAGGAAGAUUGUUAGCCAACUUUCUGUUUCUCCCACCCAACAACAAGUGGAUCUCAUUAUAUCAGCCUGCUUUAUUACCAUUUUCACAGCAUCUAAUAGGCAUCUAAACUAAACUUCAUGAUCCAGCUCUUUGGAGAAAGGAUUUAUUUCCAAUAACCUAAAUACAGAAGAAAUCCUAAUUCUGUCCAGAAUUUUUUUUUUUGGUUUUGCAAAUUUUAAGAUUUGAGAUGAACUGUUAUAUAUAUAUAUAUUAUAAUGUUACUUUUUGGAGGUUUUCUUACCUUAAAUUUGUCAUUUCCCUGUGAAGUUCAGUGUGCAUGUAGGAGGGGCUUGUGAGAUUAUGCCUUGUCUCUGACGGUGGAGCUGAUCUCUUAGAAAUGGCUCAUAGUGUUGUGGGGAAUAGGACAGGCUGAGGUUCCAGGUUGAAAUGGCAGUAAGUGUUUCCUUUAAAGUGUCCUAUCCCUGGUAAAUAUUAACAGUGGAGAAUAGAAUUAGUUCUUUAGUGAGAAUAUUUGAAUCAUAAGGUACCUUUGUAUCUCCUUUUACUGAUGGAAGACCAAGGCCCAAAGAAGGGAAGGGAUCUGAGAAAAUCAGUGGCAAAGAUAGGACUAGAAGACCCAAGUUUCUUGAUUUCCCAUCUGGCGAUCUUUUUCUUUUUCUUUUCCUUUCUUUCUUUCUUUUUUUUUUUUUUACUGUGAUAAAAAACAAAAACAAAACAAAAAACAACCCAUAAAAUAUGCCAUCUUGGUAAUUUUUAAGUGUACAGUUAAUAUUCACAUUGUUGUGAAACAUCUGAGAUUUUAUGCCUAUUAAACAACAACUCCCCUUUUCUAAAACUCUUCCAAAGGCCCCUGGUUGCCACCAUUCUACUUUCUAUGAAUUUGACUAUUUUAGAUACCUCAUAUAAGUGGGAUCAUAUAUUAUAUGUCUUUUUGUGACUGGCUUAUGUCACUUGGCAUAAUGUCCUCAAAGUUCAGUCCCUAUGCAGCAUGUGAUAGCAUUUCUUUCCUUUUUAUGGCUGAAUUAUAUAUGUAUAUACCACAUUUCGUUUAUUCAUUCAUCCAUCAGUGGCCAUUUGAGUUGCUUCCACCUCUUGGCUGUUAUCCAUAGUGCUGCUAUGAACAUGGGUUUGCAGAUCCCUCUUUGAGAUUCUGUUUUCAAUUCUUUGGAUAUGUACCCAGAAGUGGGAUUCCUGGAUCAUACAGUAGUUCUGUUUUUAAUAUUUUGAGGAACUGCCUUGAUGUUUUUCUUAUUGGUUGAACUAUUUUACAACUCAGUACACAAGGGUUCCUUCCGAAUUCUCCACAUCCUCACCAACACUUAUUUUUCUCUUUUUUGAUAGUAGUCAUCCUAAUGGGGGUGAGGUGGUAUCUCAUUGUGGUGUUGCUGUGCAUUUAUUUAUUGAUUAGUGAUGUUAAGCAUCGUUUCAUAUGCUUAUUGGCCACUUCUGUAUCACCUCUAGAGAAAUGUCUAUUCAAGCCCUUUGACCAUUUUUUAAUCAGGUUACUCGAUGUUUUUAGUUGCUGAAUUGUAGGAGUCCUUUAUAUAUUCUGAAUAUUAAUCCAUUAUAAGAUAUAUGAUUUGCAAAGAUUUUCUCCCAUUCCAUACACAUAGUACCAUUUGUCUAUUUUUGCUUUUGUUCACUGCUUUUUGGUGUCAUAUCCAAGAAAUCAUUACCAAGUCUACUGUCCAGCUUUUCCUCCAUGUUUUCUUCUAGGAGUUUUAUAGUCUUAGUCUUACUAGGUCUUUAAUCCAUUUGAGUUAAUUUUUGGAUAUGGGAUAAGGCCCCAGCUUCACUUUGGAAUAUGCAUAUCUGUUUGGUUAUCCCAGUACUGUUUGUUGAAGAGACUGUUCUUUCCCCAUUGAGUGGUCUUGGCAGUCUUGUCAAAAAUCAUUUGACUAUUUAUGUGAAGGUUUAUUUUUGGGCUCUCUAUUCUAUUCCACUGGUCUAUUUGUCUUUACGGCAGUACUAAGCUGUUUCAAUUACUGCAGCUUUGUAAUUGGGGAGUGUGAGUUCUCCAAUUUUGUUCUUCUUCAAAAUUGUUUUGGCUAGUCAGUGUCUAUGAGAUUCCAUAUGAAUUUUAAGGUGAUUUUUUUUAUUUCCUAAAAAAAAAAGCCAUGGGAAUUUUGAUAGAGAUUAUAUUGAAUCUGUGGAUUACUUUGGGUAGUAUGGACAUCUUAAGCAUCCAGUGAUCUUUAAGAUAAUAUGUUACUAUCUCAUGUUCACUUUUAGAUUUUCAUAUUGUGGUUGAUUCAGUAUAUUUAUUUCAAUUAUAAUGUUUCAAAUAUUUCAAUGGUACAGAAAAAUAUAGAGAAUUAUUUAUUUUUUCAGCCAAUAUUUGAUUGCAUACUCUGUGCUUAUCUACAAUAAAGAUUUAAUAAAUGUUGA